GCUUUGGGUCACGAGGCUUCACGGAGGAGGUGGGUGAGUCAUGCGCGCGCGCGGAGGGGAGUGUAGCGGGGGGGGAGGGGAGGAAAGGGGGGCGGGGAUGAUGCAAUGUUUGGCAACCGGUGUCUGCACGCGCACGCGCAGGGGACACCGAGGGUGGUGGGAGGUGCGGAGGGUGGGGGAGAGGAGAGAGGGCGGGGCGCCAGCUCCCGGCGCCCAACGGCCCCAACGGCUAUCAGCCUUGGUCGCCCCUAGUCGGUCGUGAGCCUCUUUGCCGCUUGUCUCCCCCAGAAGCUGCUGUUCCGCCCACCUAGCUUUACCCGCCGUUUUACCCCCACUAUAAGGGACUCCCAUAUUUCUUGGCCCCUCCCAGCUAAUGGGCACAUAGGCCUUUUGAACUUUUCUUUUUAAAGUUGGUAUCCAUCCACUGGGAUUGUCGACAUCUCGAGUCUUCUUAAAGAGGUCUCCUGGCCGGGCUCAGUGGCUUACGCCUGUAAUCCCAGCACUUUGGGAGGCUGAGGAGAGCGGAUCACUUGAGGUCAGGAGUUCGAGAUCAGCCUGACCAACAUGGUGAAACCCCGUCUCUACUAAAAAUACAAAAAUUAGCCGGGUGUGGUGAUGCGCGCCUGUAAUCCCAGCUACUCUGGAGGCAGAGGCAGAAGAAUCGCUUGAACCCUGGAGGCGGAUGUUGCAGUGACCGAGAUCGCGCCACUGCACUCCAGCCUGGGUGACAGAGCGAGACUACGUUUCACCAAAAACAAAAAACAAAACAAACAAACAAAAAAACGGGGGUGGUCUCCUGUUCUAGCCCCGUAAAUCUCCCAAAAGGGGCCGAGGUACUGGAAUCCCUUGGUAGUCAUUUUCCGCUUCUCUCAGAACAGCGCCCUUGACUUUUACCUUGUAGUUGGUAAGCCCUCAGCCUGCCAGAAGUCAUGUAUUUUGCCCAGUGGACCCGAUUCUGUUUGGCCACCUAUUUUCCCCCACGGUACUCCUAUGGCUUUCUCCAAGACCCUCUCUUGCUGUACCAGACAGCAAGUCCUGUGACUCCCUGUGUGAGGAGCGCGGCACAGGCCUGCCUCCUAGGUGUUCGGGUCGAGAUUUACAGCGGAGUCUCAUCCCGGGACGUGUGAGUGCACUUCAGCGCAGGACUGCCCUGGACUGGGGAGACCGGAGCCGCGAUUUUAGACUCAACUCCCCAUCACUUGCCAAGGGAUCUUACCGUCCUUGUUUGUAAAUUAAAGAUAAAAGUUGUGAAGGUGUGGGCUAAGCUGGUGGCCCCGGCUUUAGACUGGACCCCACAAUGUUUGCAGAGAUGUUCAGGCACGCGGGAGCUGAUUACACACAAUGAAUGGGGGCAAUGAGAGCAGUGGAGCAGACAGAGCUGGGGGCCCUGUGGCCACAUCUGUCCCCAUCGGCUGGCAGCGCUGUGUGCGAGAGGGUGCUGUGCUCUACAUCAGUCCAAGUGGCACAGAGCUGUCUUCCUUGGAGCAAACCCGGAGCUACCUCCUCAGCGAUGGGACCUGCAAGUGCGGUCUGGAGUGUCCACUUAAUGUCCCCAAGGUUUUCAACUUUGACCCUUUGGCCCCGGUGACCCCGGGUGGGGCUGGGGUGGGGCCAGCAUCAGAGGAGGACAUGACCAAGCUGUGCAACCACCGGCGGAAAGCUGUUGCUAUGGCAACUCUGUACCGCAGCAUGGAGACCACCUGCUCACACUCUUCUCCUGGAGAGGGAGCGAGCCCCCAAAUGUUCCACACUGUGUCCCCAGGGCCCCCCUCUGCCCGCCCUCCCUGUCGAGUUCCUCCUACAACUCCACUUAAUGGGGGUCCUGGCUCCCUUCCCCCAGAACCACCCUCAGUUUCCCAGGCCUUUCCCACUCUAGCAGGCCCUGGGGGGCUUUUCCCCCCAAGGCUUGCUGACCCAGUCCCUUCUGGGGGCAGUAGCAGCCCCCGUUUCCUCCCAAGGGGCAAUGCCCCCUCUCCAGCCCCACCUCCUCCACCUGCUAUCAGCCUCAAUGCUCCCUCAUACAACUGGGGAGCUGCCCUCAGAUCCAGCCUGGUGCCCUCUGACCUGGGCUCUCCUCCGGCCCCUCAUGCCUCCUCCUCACCACCUUCAGACCCUCCUCUCUUCCACUGUAGUGAUGCCUUAACACCCCCUCCCCUGCCCCCGAGCAAUAAUCUCCCCGCCCACCCUGGUCCUGCCUCUCAGCCACCAGUGUCUUCAGCCACUAUGCACCUGCCCCUGGUCCUGGGGCCCCUGGGAGGGGCCCCCACGGUGGAGGGGCCUGGGGCACCCCCCUUCCUUGCUAGCAGCCUACUCUCUGCAGCGGCCAAGGCACAGCAUCCCCCACUACCCCCUCCCAGCACUUUACAGGGCCGAAGGCCCCGUGCCCAGGCACCCUCAGCUUCCCACUCCUCAUCACUUCGUCCCUCUCAGCGUCGUCCCCGCAGACCCCCUACUGUAUUUCGAUUGCUAGAAGGGAGAGGCCCUCAAACCCCUAGACGGAGCCGUCCUCGGGCCCCUGCUCCUGUCCCCCAACCCUUUUCUCUCCCGGAGCCAUCCCAACCAAUUCUCCCUUCUGUGCUGUCCCUGCUGGGACUCCCCACCCCUGGCCCUUCCCACUCUGAUGGAAGCUUUAACCUUUUGGGGUCAGAUGCACACCUUCCUCCUCCCCCAACCCUCUCCUCAGGGAGCCCUCCCCAGCCCAGGCACCCCAUCCAGCCCUCCCUGCCUGGGACCACCAGUGGCAGCCUCAGCAGUGUGCCAGGUGCCCCUGCCCCACCAGCUGCCUCCAAAGCCCCAGUAGUCCCCAGCCCUGUGCUUCAAAGCCCAUCCGAAGGACUGGGGAUGGGGGCAGGCCCGGCCUGCCCUCUGCCUCCCCUGGCUGGUGGAGAGGCUUUCCCUUUCCCCAGCCCUGAGCAGGGCCUGGCACUGAGUGGAGCUGGCUUCCCUGGGAUGCUUGGGGCCUUGCCUCUCCCUCUGAGUCUGGGGCAGCCUCCACCUUCUCCAUUGCUCAACCACAGUUUAUUUGGUGUGCUGACUGGGGGAGGAGGACAACCUCCCCCUGAGCCCCUGCUACCCCCACCAGGAGGACCUGGUCCUCCCCUAGCCCCAGGAGAGCCUGAAGGGCCUUCGCUUUUGGUGGCUUCCUUGCUUCCUCCACCACCCUCAGACCUUCUUCCACCUCCUUCAGCACCUCCCAGCAACCUCCUUGCCUCUUUCCUGCCCCUGUUGGCUCUGGGCCCCACAGCUGGGGAUGGGGAGGGAUCUGCAGAGGGAGCCGGGGGUCCAAGUGGGGAGCCAUUUUCAGGCUUGGGAGACCUGUCCCCCCUACUUUUCCCCCCACUUUCAGCCCCCCCUACCCUCAUAGCUUUAAAUUCUGCGCUGCUGGCUGCCACCCUGGAUCCCCCCUCGGGGACACCCCCCCAGCCCUGUGUCCUGAGUGCCCCCCAACCUGGACCACCUACCUCCAGUGUCACCACGGCAACUACUGACCCGGGGGCCUCCUCUCUGGGCAAGGCCCCCUCCAACUCAGGGAGACCCCCCCAACUCCUUAGCCCUCUGCUGGGUGCCAGCCUGCUGGGUGACCUGUCUUCACUGACCAGCAGCCCUGGAGCCCUCCCCAGCCUGUUGCAGCCUCCUGGCCCUCUUCUCUCUGGCCAGUUGGGGCUGCAGCUCCUCCCUGGGGGGGGAGCUCCUCCACCCCUCUCAGAGGCUUCUAGUCCCCUAGCCUGCCUGCUACAGAGUCUCCAGCAGAUCCCUCCAGAGCAGCCAGAAGCCCCCUGUCUACCCCCCGAGAGCCCUGCCUCAGCCCUCGAACCAGAGCCUGCCAGGCCUCCCCUCAGUGCCUUAGCCCCACCCCAUGGUUCUCCCGACCCCCCAGUCCCUGAGCUGCUCACUGGGAGGGGGUCAGGGAAACGGGGCCGGAGGGGAGGAGGGGGACUUAGGGGCAUUAAUGGUGAGGCCAGGCCAGCCCGGGGCCGAAAGCCUGGCAGCCGGCGGGAGCCUGGCCGACUGGCCCUCAAAUGGGGGACACGUGGUGGCUUCAAUGGACAAAUGGAAAGGUCCCCAAGAAGAACCCACCAUUGGCAGCAUAAUGGGGAGCUGGCUGAAGGGGGUGCUGAGCCCAAGGAUCCACCCCCUCCCGGGCCCCAUUCUGAGGACCUUAAGGUGCCCCCGGGAGUAGUCAGAAAGUCUCGUCGUGGCCGUAGGAGAAAAUACAACCCUACCCGGAACAGCAAUAGCUCCCGCCAGGACAUUACCUUGGAACCCAGCCCUACAGCCCGAGCAGCUGUCCCUCUGCCUCCCCGGGCCCGCCCUGGCCGUCCUGCCAAAAACAAGAGGAGGAAACUGGCCCCAUAGCAGCCAUACCUGGAGCUGGAUCUGACCCUGAUUGGGGAGAGCUGAGUGCUGAGCCUUGGGAGCCCCUGCCAGCCACCUGCACCUGUGGACAGUGGGUGGGGGCACUACUCCCCACUCAGAGCACAAAUGCAACUCCUUCCCCUACAAUCCCAUCCUGAGCCAUUGCAGGGGGCAGGGAAGUUCACCCCCCCCCACCACCCCCCCGCCCCCCCGAAGCCAUGUCACUGAAAAGGCCUGGGGGGGAUGGUAUAUGGCCCUUUCCCCACCAGGCGCUAAGGGGAACACCCCCUUCCCCAGGUCUUUUAUUUGUUUAAGUUAUUUUUGCACAAAUGACUCUUUUAUAUUUAAUUCGAUUUCAUUGCCUCCCUUCUUAAAGCCAACAGGCUCAGUUUACAAACCUGUGAGCUACUGUUGGCUGCUGCCCUCCUUCCCAGUGAAAGGUACAAAGCAAUAAGCAUCAUGCAUCCUCCCCUUACCCCUCCAACACCCCUCUGCCUCUGGCUCAGGUUGCUCAAAGCACAGAUCCUCUCUUACCCCGUCCCCAGGUUUGAAACACAUAGCCUCAUUUCAAGGUGUAGCCAGGUUCCCCCGACUUUCCUCUGGGAUAUAAAAAAGGGGGUAAGGGGGCAAAGAGAGCCCUCUGGGCCUCUCCUCCCAUACACACUACACUGCCCCUUCUCCCCCCAUCAAAACGCUCAGAGACGUUGUGAUGAUGCGACUGAGGAUUAUGCAACGUGGUCCAACCGGAGCGGCCAGCAUGACCAGCUGUCCAGGGGCUGCCUCCUGCCUUUUCUUUUGUAAAGACAAGACCCUUGGGAGUUUUAAUUCUGUUUUGUACUUGCCCUGUGGGGCCUCCACUGCUUUUCUAUGGGAGACACUCUUAAUUUAACAGAUGAGAAUAUUUUGAAACUCUG